UCAUGAUCCGCCCGCCUUGGCCUCCCAAAAUGCUGGGAUUACAGGCAUGAGCUACCAUGCCCAGCUGAGUACCGUCUUAUUUAGAGAAGACACCCACUUUCAUUUUUGCCCCUCAUUUCAUGGGGAAAGACCAGCCCACAGUUUAAGUAAGUAUUCCUAACAGGCGAAUCCGCAGUUCUAUAUGGGCUCUGAGGUCUCGUGCACAGAAGCCAAAGGACUGGAGGGAUGUGACCAGAUUUGGGAAUCAGGCAAGCUGGCUCCAGGCAGGCUGAGAUCAAGCUGAUAACAAGGAGAUUAAUGAGGGCCUGCAACCUCCUCAGUCUUGUAUUAGGGAGGAGGGUUUUCAAAUCAAUGCUGGUCUGGCUGGCUUAAUGGUACCUAAUCUUACCUUUUGAAGCUCACGCAUUUGGGAGUUGAGAUCAAUUGAGAUAAAAUAAAGUAAAAUGUGUUGACUUUGGGAUUUGUGGUCUUCAUCAGAGUCCCAUUGUGUAGUGUUGUUUUUAUUUUCUGUCUUGGAAAUAGGCAGAGAUUAGCUGCCGGAGAGGGUUGUUCUGUCUGGACUAGGUGGUCUAUUUACUUUUGUUCUGCUUUUUUCAUUUUCCGCUCGAUGAUUCUUCAUGAGGGAAGGGCCCAUUUCUUUCCUGUUCAUUUCUGUAUAGCGAGUGCAUGACACCUGGUACAUGCUCAGUAACUAUUUCUCAAAUGCAGCAUUGCAGCAUCACCAGCACAGACUGUGUGCCACGAGCCACCCUGCUGGAAAAGCCAAUCUGCUCCUGAUUAGGUGCAAAAACAGCAGCCUUAUAAGGCACUCACAGUGCCCCUGGAAAAAGGCGUCAGGACGGUUUCCUGGUACCUGGUUUCUGUGAUGGUUACCAUGAGCUUUGUGCAGUCAUUGCAAAGCUGUGUGUGAGCAAAGUGCAUCCGAUCCAUUUUACAGGUGCUUACAAGCCCUGUGCUGAGUGCUGGCGACUGAAAAGAUGAGUACAGCAUAGGGAAGGUGCUCAUGGAGUUUGUGAUCUGGUGGGGGAGCGAGUUGUGUAAUGACGAGGAAUGUGUCUGGAGGUGAGAGUUUCGGGGUCUGGGCUUUGGUUGUGGAUUUGCCACCACCAGGCCAUUGCCCUAAGGGCAGGCCCUAACGUCUUUGGGCCUCAGUUUUCGCAUUUAUAAAAAGUGGACUCAAUGGACCUACAGGUCUUCACUUGCUCUAGAGCAACAAAACUGGAGAGCUGUCUCAAGGAGUUUUCCUGUGCAGUGGAGUUCAGCCUCACUGGAAAUAGCAAAUCCAUUUGCUGCUACACCCCUAAAUUCCUUGCCCUGAAAUUUUAGAGCAGGGCAAUAAAUAGGUGUUGGUCUAUUUUCACCUACCACCUGCUCUACAUUAAAAAGAAAAGAAAGCUGCUAUAUGGCAAGAGGAAGACAAGCUAAUAUACUGGGUAUCUGCUCUUUGCCAGGCACUGCAUUUGACAUUUUCACAUCUCAAUGGAACGUCCUGAUAAACUUGCAGGACGGGGAGCAACAGCAUCGUCACUGCUGCACCCUUCAGUCCACUUAGAGGACCGUUGUGUCACAGCAGGAUUGGUGUUCCCGUCAAAUGACAUCCUGUAUACCGAGUUUUAGAAAAGCACAUGAGUGCACGUAACGGGAUGUAGAAAAGCUAUUUUCAAGCAUAGUUAAAUGUGGUGAUUUUGGAAGCCUUCUUCACUUAACUAUGAGGAAAAUUCAUUAUCACCAACAAACAUCUUAUGAGAGUAGUAUAUCAGCCUAAUUGCCAUCCCUGACCUCCCAUGGUGAGCUGACGUGUAAUAAAAACAAAAAUAACAAUAGCGUGCUCAUAGUACUGCUGAUUCCUACCGUAGGAGCUCCAAAGAGGGGGUUCCCUACCAAGGACUAGGGAUGAGAGAAGGCAGGAUUUGGGGACUUGAAGGAAGAGCCCAAGGACUUGAGCUGGAAAAAGAAUGACAUUGGUGACCUAGAUGGAGAGAAUGGCCAGGACCAAGAAAGUUUCCCAUGUGCAAGGAGGAGCUGUUCUCACAUUUGUGACGCGGCUGCCACAGACUCUGGCAGUGCCUAGAGGUGGAGGAAAGUAGGGGAGGACAGAGGGCUUGGAGCCAGGCUGUCAAGGGCUGAAGAACUCAGACUUGAUUCUUUGAGGGUUUCUUUGGUUUAACAUGGGGUCCGGAGACCUCUAAAGAAUCUGUGAUGGGGUUCAGAUCCACGAACCCCUUGAAAUUGUAGGCAUUUUUCUGAGCAGAUGGUUCAAACAUUUCAAAGGAUUCCCAAAGGGACCCACAAAAGCUUAAGAGGAGCCGCUGUGGACAGUUGGGACCCUUGAAGUGCUUUGACCAAAGGUAUGUGCAGACGAUGCAUCAGUUGCUUGGAGGGGGCAGGUGCCGGGAAGACCACCCAUGGGAGUAGCAUUGAGGGUCGGGCGGGGGUGUUGAAAAGGAAGAGGGAGUUAGGAAGCCAUGGUUAUGAAGAAGAAAUGACAGCUCUGCAGCACUCUCGGGACAGUCAGUAACAGCUGCAUGAACAACUGAGCCCACUGUGGGUGCAGGACAUCAGAGGGGAAGCUGUGUGUUAUGGUCCUAUAGUGAGUUUGGUUUUAAACAUGAUCAUUUUAAGAGGCUGAGUUUAUCUAUGUGGAAAUGAAGACAAUUUAAAAAUUAUUAAGCCACCACUUACUGGAGCAACUAGGGGAUAAGAGGGCAGCAGAACCACCCCUCUUUCAUUUUAUAGGUACAGCCACUGAGGCCCUGAGAUAGGAAGUGACUUGUCCACAGUCACCUCAAUGGUGGGCAGCUGGGGACCAAUUCGUAAGAGAAUAACAGGAGAGAAGUUAGGCUGGAGGUUAGGCUAGAUCUGAAGCCCUCUGGGGGAGAUGGCAGUUGAAGCUCUUAGUGUAGAUAAAAUCUCUAAAGUAGAAAAGACCCCAGAAUUAAGCUUGGGUCUUUGCUCUGAUUUAGAGAAUUGGAAACAGAAACCAAGGUAGCAAAGGCCAUGCAGAAGGGCAGUGAGGGAAGUACGAGGCAACCAAGAGGAAGAAGCAAGGCAAGACAGGCAGGUGCUCCCGGUGGGAGGGUCCUUACAGACGAGGGCCUCAGGCCAGGUUGUCGGCAGAUCCCCAGUGGCAUUUGAGAGAUACCUCCUUCCUUGGAAUUGUGGGGUGAAGCGAGAUUCCAAAGAGAGGUCUCUGAUAAAGGGGCCAGAGAGGGCAUACUGGCCUUGCCGGAGGUGUGAAAAGGAAGGAGAAGUGGGUGAGGGGUGGAGGCAGGCAGGAGAAUAAUAUUUUAAAAAUAAAAGAGUGCAUCUGUAAAAAUAACUAAAGAAAUGAGAGGAGGGAAGGAAGGGGGGAGAGGUUCAAUGAUAGGGUCACAGUCAGGUGAAAAUGAGACCAAAUGGCAGAGGUGGGGAGGGGAAGAGGAGGGAUGAAGGUUCAGAGGAGAGAUGAAGGGGUGAGCAGGGCCUGGAAACAUGGUAAAUUUUAAAGGAGGGAAGAUUGGGAUCCUCUAACCCAUUAGGCUCUUCUUGCCUUUCAAGUUGUGGCCCAUGCAGACCUCUCUGCCUGAUAUUCUUCCCACAGCCCUUUGCAAGGCUGGUUCCCCAUCUUCCUUCAGAGUUCUGACAGAUGCCAUCUCUUGAAACAGCCCUUCCUGUCCACUCCCCAGUAUCCAUGCAGUCUGGUAUGCACCACCAUUUGCCUCUGUGUUUUUGUUUUUGUUUUGUUUGUUUGUUUGUUUUGAGACAGGGUCUUGCUCUGUCACCCAGGCUGGAGUGCAGUGGUGCGAUCUUGGCUCACUGCAACCACUGCCUCCCAGGUUCAAGCAAGUCUCAUGCCUCAGCCUCCCAAGCAGCUGGGAUUACAGGCGCAUGCCACCACACCCAGCUAAUUUUUUGUAUUUUUAGUAGGAAUGGGCUUUCACCAUGUUUGCCAGCUGGUAUCAAACUCUUGGCCUCAAGUGAUUCGCCCACCUCGGCCUCCCAAAGUGCUGGGAUUACAGGCGUGAGCCACUGCACCCAGCCCUUGCCUCUGUUUUCUUCUCAGCAUUGCCCAGUAAUGGGUAGGUGUUUAUAGCUCUGUUCCUUUGCUGGCUGGUGGGGGGUGUAGGGUGGGGAGGGGGGUGAGUGUGCGUUUGUUUCAUGUCCCCAAAUUUCUAUUUUAAGCACCUUCAAACUGGAGACAAUUUGUCUCCAUUCCCACUGCAACCCUAGAGCCCUGCUCAGUGCCCGUUGCAGAGUAGGUGCUCCAUGAUGCUCGAAAAAGAAAGGCAUGUUAAUUGAAACAAAGAGAAGGGAAGGUAGAACUCAGCCAUAACCUAUCCUCCUCUCAGAAAACUUUUAAUCAGAACAGUAAUUACAUUAAAAUGAAAAUAGCAUCUGCCAGCUGUUGAUAUGUUUUCAUUACCUUUUUUACUCUUCACAGUUCACCCUUCUGAAGGAGUGAGGAAACUCAGUCUGAAUAUUCUGCGAGUUAAGGUGGAGCUAGGGACCAUACCGAAGACUGUGUUCUCAUUUGCCACCUCAUUUUAUUUUUAUAGUGUUGUAUCAAAGAGGAAUUCGGGAGGCAGAGGUACAAUCAGAUCAGCUGUGAACAGCUUACAUAGCAAAUCUAAUAGAGCUGAAGUUGUAAUAAACGGCUCCUCAUCACCAGCUGUUGUUGACAGAAGUAAUGAAAGCAUCAAGCACAACAUCCAGCCAGCCUCGUCCAAAUGGAGACAUAACCAGACGCUCUCUCUGAGGAUCAGGAAGCAGAUUUUAAAGUUCUUGGAUGCUGAAAAGGACAUUUCUGUCCUAAAGGGAACCCUGAAGCCUGGAGAUAUUAUUCAUUACAUCUUCGAUCGAGACAGCACCAUGAAUGUGUCCCAGAACCUCUACGAGCUCCUCCCCAGGACUUCGCCACUGAAGAAUAAGCACUUUGGGACUUGUGCCAUCGUGGGCAACUCGGGGGUCUUGCUGAACAGCGGCUGUGGGCAGGAGAUUGACGCCCACAGCUUCGUCAUCAGGUGCAACCUGGCCCCAGUACAGGAGUAUGCCCGGGAUGUGGGGCUCAAGACAGACCUGGUAACCAUGAACCCCUCGGUCAUCCAGCGGGCCUUUGAGGACUUGGUCAAUGCCACGUGGCGGGAGAAGCUGCUGCAACGGCUGCACAGCCUCAAUGGCAGCAUCCUGUGGAUCCCUGCCUUCAUGGCCCGGGGCGGCAAGGAGCGUGUUGAGUGGGUCAACGAGCUUAUCCUGAAGCACCACGUCAACGUGCGCACUGCAUACCCCUCGCUGCGCCUGCUGCACGCCGUUCGCGGAUACUGGCUGACCAACAAAGUCCACAUCAAAAGACCCACCACCGGCCUCUUGAUGUAUACCCUGGCCACACGUUUCUGCAAACAAAUCUACCUCUACGGCUUCUGGCCCUUUCCGCUGGAUCAGAACCAGAACCCAGUCAAGUACCACUAUUAUGACAGCCUCAAGUAUGGCUACACCUCCCAGGCCAGCCCGCAUACCAUGCCCUUGGAGUUUAAGGCCCUCAAGAGCCUACAUGAGCAGGGGGCUUUGAAACUGACUGUCGGCCAGUGCGAUGGGGCCACGUAGGGUGGGCACCCCAUGGGACUCAGUGGCUCACAUUUCCUGCCAGCUACACCACAGGCAGAUGGGAGUCGGGGUGGCACAAACAAUAGAACAAGCAGGCUAGUGGUUUUCUUUGUUAAAGUGUAAAACAGUGACCAGAAUAUAUAUAUCUAUACCUGCAUAUAUAUAUUGACCUGAGUAUUUAUAACUGUGUGGUGUUCAUCUAGCAUUAGGCAGAUAGGCCACAGGAAGAAGGUGUGGAGAACCCACCUGAACCAGAUUGAGACUCAAUCCAUCUUUGGGGGUGGAAGGACUUGACAUGAAAAGAAGCCAGUCCCAUGACUUUGGAUGACAAACUGCCUCCUGGCUUGGAGGGAUCUUUGGGCUCAUGGAUGAAUGGCGAGCCACCUGUUGUCAGCUGCCCCAAGCCUCUGGGAUAUGUGGAUUCGGAGAAAGCUGAGGCCCAGAGGGGACACUCGACCCAGUCUAAAGUGGGUGCCAUUCACGGAGGAGAGGGAGGUUGGAGACUUCAACCGGGCAAAGGAGCACAAGGAAACCAAGCAGCAGAGGCCCCAUCAGCACAGAGGGCCUCGUUCCACGAACGUAGAGUUUGACUGCCUAAGGGACAGCACGAAUGACUCACAUGUUUCAGACAGGCCUCCACGGCUAUGGAGAGAAGGCUGGAGGAGACACAAUGGAUGGUUCAUGUUCUGGCUUAGCAAGAGCCACCAAGAACUUUGGGUGAAGCAAGCAGAUGACAAUGAAGAGGAGUAAUGUUCCGAAUCAUGUUUUUGAAAAAUCAAGACCUCCUGUUAAGGGCCCACUUGACCCUAGAAUAAGGCAGGAGAGUGUCUAAAAUCUAGCUGCUUUGGGUGUUUUUUAAAGCAAUGUGAGUCCACUGAGGAGGAAGAGACCCUGGGAUUUCACCCUCUGGGUUAGUCUCUGUCUCACCCUGUUAGAAUGUCACGAGGGACUGUACUGUCCCCUCUGUCACCAGGGAAGCCACAAUGAGAGCUUGAAAGGGUGCUGUCAAGAUAAAUGUCAUCCUUCUUAAAAUACAUAUGAUUGCCUUUUUGGGUGCCUCACAGAGCCCCAGAGUGUGAGACCUGAAAGAAUGUUCAGCAUCUAGCUCCAUGUCCCUGCAACCACUCUCUGUUUGCCUUCUGCAUUCUGCACUCUGCGGGGCCUUUGCAGCCAGACUGCUGUGUCAAUGUUACUUUCUUGUCACUUUCCUACCCUGAUGGUCACACUAGCCCACCCCAAGCUCCGACAUUGAGGUUUUCAUCUCUGCAGGGAGAGGUUCCAAUGUCCACCCCACCCCCAGGUACCCGCCUCUUCCCACAGAAGCAAUUUUAGAAUUUUGCAAAAUUCUUUUCCCCUUAUUGAGAUUAAUAUUUAAGAUUAAAAAAAAAAUACCCAAAGCCAAAUGCAGUUCCAAAUAGUGGACAUAAUCUCCCAGGGAAAUCUGGGCUCGAGGCCUACAACUUAGGGGCUGGAAUCACAGGUCUCACAUAGAGAAAUAGCCAGCUUGAAUUUGUUAGUCGUAUUCCUUCACCUGAUGAAUAACAGUGUUUUAAAACAUAUUUGAAAGGUAAGUAAAAAACUACCAUCUUGAAGGUGAAGGGAGUUAAGAAAAGUAAUCAAGACCUGCUCCUAAGCAUAUGAGACCAGAUGUAAUUAAUCAAUGGCAAUGCAGAACAGGACCUUGGCUCUAAAUUAAUGGUUGACCGGAAGGGAUUGGAGGCGGCAGAACCAUUAACCCUACACAAGAACACUCCAGCCCAAAACCGUGAGGAAGGUGAUAUAUCUCUGCAUUUUCCCUUGUUGUUGCUUGAAGUCUGUGAUUGGGGAUUUGCGUUAUAAAAUGAAUAUUUUAAAAAGCAACAGCCCUAAUAGCCUCUGUGGGAACUGAGUGGUUUCGGACUCCUCACAGGCGGUGGAAAUAAUUAAUACCAUAUUUUAUACAUCUCCAGAGCCUUUCAUCUUGAGGAUCUCAAAGACCGUAGAAGACAUUUAAUUUCUAAAGCUUGAAGUGCCCCGAGGAGCAGGUAGAAUUUCCAGCAGGGCCUUGGUGGAUUAACCAAGGCCUUGGAUUCCAGAAUGUUUCAUGGUAAGCACUGUGGAGAACCUACAUGUCAGGUUCUGGAGUUGGCCCUGAGCUCUAUCCACCAAGCCAGCACCCCACCAUCCCUUUGCAGGGGAGUCAAAGGGCCAGAACUCCUUGGGGGACCAGAACAUGGUUUUCCUUCUGCCUAUCUUAGUCAUGGCUCCUAAAAUUGAAGCUGAUAUGAGCUGGAGUGCAAGGAGUCCUUCCACCCUGCCUUCAGGUUCUCUCUGGAGAAAGGUUAGAGACCCCAGGACAAUCAACAUGUGCACCGUUCCCCUCCUCGGCUUGAGUCCUGCACUACCAAAAUGGCCUGGCCAUUUGAUGGCGGAGCUCCAGGGGCCUUGGCUUUCUCUGGCUCAUUGUCCUUCUCCAUCUGGGCCAAUUGUCCUUCCCUGCCCAUUCAGAGUUCAAUUUGAGCCUCCACUGCAGUUCCUGGUGUGGGCCAGCUGGUGUUGGGUGGCCCCAGGGAGUCACACAGUCUGUACCCGGCCCCGAGAUCCUCUGCUGUAACUGCAGGGUCACAGGCAUCCCGGGAGAAUGGGCCUCCACCCUCAGCCAGCCCUCACUGCUGACAGGCACCCCUCUGUCACCUCCUGCCACCUGUCAGAUACCCAGCCUGCCCGCCAUCAGCCACCCGAGUGGUUCCGACCUCCAUUCACCUCAAGCCCCAACAGGCCCCUGUCAUUCCACUUCAUGGAAGAGACGGAGCCUUCUGAAAUGAGAUCUACCCUGAAAAUCUCUUCUCCUUCCCCUUUCUGAGAAACGUCAUCCCCACCAGUUAACGUUUCCUGUACACCCUCACCCUCUCUCGUCCAUCUCUGUUGCCUCUGCACAUCAGCACACACUGACUCCACCUGGGCUGGCUCCUGCCGCCUCUUCCCUACCUCCUCCACUAGCCGCAGGAAGGGCCUCCAGCACCCACAACUGCCCUUCCUCUUGAUGCCCCUCGGCUUCCCCCCAGCCUGGCAGCAGCGUCCCAGCGCCUCCACAUUGCCCCUCUCACCUCCCAGCUCUCCACGCCACUUGGCUCUGCAGCGACCCCUCCUAGACGCUCCCUGGCCCCUCGGCACCCAGAAUGCCACAUUCUUGUGUUUUUUUCCUCCUUCUUUCCCAAUCCCUCUCAACCAUGUAUUUAUUUAUAUAUGUAUGUAUUUUUUUAUUUAUUAUUUAUUUAUUGAAACCCCUACUUUGAUUGACAAAGGAAUCAAGGUAGAUCUGACCAGUAUUCCCCUCUCUUCUCCUUGUCCCACCACAUGGACAUGCCUUACACUGGCGUCCUCUCCUGAGUCCCUCCGCACUCUCCAUCAGCAACCUCACACCUGCCUUCAGACCCGGCUGCAACUUCCUAAGCUGCCCCUGCCCCAGCUCCUCUCUGCAACCCAGCCCUCUCCUGAGCUCUAGGCUGGGAUUACACCCGCUGGAGGGACACUCACCCCAUCUGCUCCCACGGCAGCACCAUCAACUCAACAAGUCAGAAGCCAAGUGGAUCAUCUGUGUCCCCUUCCCCCACAAUCCCUCCUUUUUCUAGUAAAAGACCCGUGAUCCCGUCAGCCACCCAGUCUGAGAUGCUGACGUUAUCUUCGACUAUUCUUCCCUGUCCUGCCUUGCUAAUUCUUCCCACUAGCACUAAUCUCGACUCUUUGUCACUUGGACUAUUUCAGCAACAGUCUCAUCUCCCAGAUUACCUCUGUGCACACUGACACGUGGUCCCGUCCAUCCUGAACAUGCACAGUGAUUUUCCUCUCCCGUUGCACACAAACCUUUAAAAGUUCCCCGGCCCGUGAACAAAUGUACAAUUCUCUAUUCUGACAUUACAGACCACCGGAUAAGGCCCCAUUCUUCCUUUACACCCUCCCCUGGUCAGCCUAGGAGAGUUGUUUUUCCUGGAAAGGGUGCCUGCGUUUUACUGUCUCUGUGCCUUUGGUCUUGCUAUCCCCAUCCCCUGGAAUGCUCCCUUUUCUUCCCUUCAAAGCCCAUGCGGAAACCACGUCCUUCAUGAAGCCCUCCCUGAUGUACCAACCACUGGGAUCUCUCCCUCUGCUGAACCACCGUAGCACUUUAUUUGUACCUUUCUCAUGGCACUUACCAUAUUCUGCCUUGUAUUAUAGUUAUUUGUGCACUUGUCCUUUGACUGUUCUUAGACUGUAAGCUUGCCAAGGGCAGGGACUGUGUUUUAUUCAUCUGUAUCCAUCACAGCACUAGGCGUGGUGCAUAGCACACAGCAGUUGCUCAAUAAAUGUUUGUUGGAUUAAAUCCUUAA